GUCCCUGUCUGGAAGCACAGCUGAAGAUGGCGAGCCCGGCGCCUCCGGAGCACGCCGAGGAGGGAUGCCCGGCUCCUGCCGCCGAGGAGCAGGCGCCGCCGUCGCCGCCACCGCCCCAGGCAUCCCCCGCAGAGCGGCAGCAGCAGGAGGAGGAAGCGCAGGAAGCUGGGGCGGCGGAGGGCGCGGGGUUGCAGGUGGAGGAGGCCGCGGGCCGGGCGGCGGCCGCGGUAACCUGGCUGCUCGGGGAGCCGGUGCUGUGGCUGGGCUGCCGCGCCGACGAGCUGCUGAGCUGGAAGAGGCCGCUGCGGAGCCUGCUCGGCUUCGUCGCUGCCAACCUGCUGUUCUGGUUCCUUGCAUUGACUCCAUGGAGAGUAUAUCACCUGAUUUCCGUCAUGAUACUUGGGCGUGUUAUUAUGCAAAUAAUAAAGGAUAUGGUUUUGUCUAGAACAAGAGGUGCACAGUUGUGGAGAAGCCUCAGUGAAAGGGCUUUAUGGCGCUCCCAAUGUCAGCCAGCUGCGGUGCCAGGAGCUAGGGUGAUGUCAGGCCCCUGCUGUCACGGAGCACACAGCCCAGGUGUGGAGACAGACCCCAAGGUGAAAAAAAACUGGGAAGUUAUCAAUUCCAAACCAGAUGAAAGACCCAGGCUCAGCCACUGUAUUGCAGAAUCAUGGAUGAAUUUCAGCAUAUUUCUUCAAGAAAUGUCUCUUUUUAAACAGCAGAGCCCUGGCAAGUUUUGUCUCCUGGUCUGUAGUGUGUGCACAUUUUUUACGAUCUUGGGAAGUUACAUUCCUGGGGUUAUACUCAGCUAUCUACUGUUACUGUGUGCAUUUUUGUGUCCAUUGUUUAAAUGUAAUGAUAUUGGACAAAAAAUUUACAGCAAAAUUAAGUCAGUUCUGCUGAAACUGGAUUUUGGAAUUGGAGAAUAUAUUAAUCAGAAGAAACGUGAGAGAUCUGAAGCAGACAAAGAAAAAAGUCACAAAGAUGACAGUGAAUUAGACUUUUCAGCUCUUUGUCCUAAGAUUAGCCUCACGGUUGCUGCCAAAGAGUUAUCUGUGUCUGACACAGACGUCUCAGAGGUAUCCUGGACUGAUAAUGGGACCUUCAACCUUUCAGAAGGAUACACUCCACAGACAGACACUUCUGAUGAUCUUGACCGACCCAGUGAGGAAGUUUUCUCUAGAGAUCUUUCAGAUUUUCCAUCUCUAGAAAAUGGCAUGGGAACAAAUGAUGAAGAUGAAUUAAGCCUUGGUUUGCCCACUGAGCUCAAGAGAAAGAAGGAACAGUUGGACAGUGGUCACAGACCAAGCAAAGAGACGCAAUCAGCAGCUGGUCUCACCCUUCCUCUGAACAGUGACCAAACCUUUCACCUGAUGAGCAACCUGGCUGGGGAUGUUAUCACAGCUGCAGUGACUGCAGCUAUCAAAGACCAGUUAGAGGGUGUGCAGCAAGCACUUUCUCAGGCUGCCCCCAUCCCAGAAGAGGACACAGACACUGAAGAAGGUGAUGACUUUGAACUACUUGACCAGUCAGAGCUGGAUCAAAUUGAGAGUGAAUUGGGACUUACACAAGACCAGGAAGCAGAAGCACAGCAAAAUAAGAAGUCUUCAGGUUUCCUUUCAAAUCUGCUGGGAGGCCAUUAAUCUAGGAAUCAGCUUGCAACAGAGCACAAAAAACACCAAAAAAAUUUCAAACAAGAAAAAAAAAAAAAAAAGGAAAAGAAAAAAAUUGAACUGUAAGCUUUAAUGAUUACUUUAGAUUUGUUUUAUUUUCCCUCCUGCAGUGAAUUAAUUGGAUAUAUAUCAGCUGACACUGAUAGAUUGAUAUUUCUGAUCGUUAUUUUUGUGUAAUAAGCAUGGAAAUGAACUUUAUACACACCACUGUGUUGUCAGAGAUAAAUAUUAGGGGUUGUUUUUAAAGCAAAAAGAAAAAAACAAAAACCAAACUAUUAAAAUCCUCCUAUAAAUAUUCUUUUUCUUUACAGUUUUUCAAGCAUGCAAAACAGUUUAUUGUAACUUACUGAAAAAUAUUAACAAUUAAUUGUGAAUACAUGCUGUUACCAGCUUCCUUAUUCCUAAUACCUGGAAAAUUUUUUUUUCAACGGAUAGAUUUUGAUGUAAAAAAGACCGAAAUUAUCAAGGUAUCUUAGUUGAAGGACUUGGGAAAUACUAUCAAAAUUAAUUUCUUAGGAAAAAAUUUAAAAGUAUAUUUAAGUACUCUGGAUAGACUGAAACGUUUCCAUGUUAUUUCUGCAGUUGUAGACUUAGGCUUAUUUGUAAAGAAGCAUGCUCCAUUGACUGCCAUCUCUAGUCUUGCAGUGGGUGGUAUUAACCCAUAGAAAGCAAGCAGUUGUGUAUCACAUAGACAAUGGUUAUGAUGUAAACAGAUUCAGUUGUUUUGUUGUUCAUUCGUCAUAUGUUUGUGAUAGGGAUGUUGGGAGCACAGCUCUAUUCUGCCUGCUCAGACUUAAGUUAGACCCUUAUCUUUUAUAUUAUGUCAUGAAAAAAGUCUCCUAAAAUUGUGAAACUAGUUCUUGAUGAGUGAUGUGAUCAUCAGCAAUAAAGAUAUAAUAACUCUGUUUUCUUAGCCUGUAUAGAGGAGAGGAACUUGCUUGGCUUUAAAAUAUAUUUAUUUGCCAUUUAAGUAUAAAUAUGGAAUCUGUUUCUUAUUGGGAAGAUAGAAUAUAUAUAUUUUCCUUUAAACUUUUUAAGGUCACUUUUAAAUAACCAAAUUUGAUUUAUGGUUUUUAACAAAGGACUAAAGAGCUGAAACCAACCUAGUUUUGUUUUUGUGAUAUAAACUUUAAGUGUCGAGGGACCAUGCCAGCAACUACCAAAAAUCUCUUAAAUCUUCAGGUACAGCUGGCAUUUUGGCAGAUGCAUAGAGACAUCUGAGACCCUCAGAAAGGAAGGAUAAUCCAAGAAUAUAGGAAAUCUGUGUUCUCUUCCUUUCAUUUUAUCCCUUAUAUUUCUAAAGACUAAUUAUAAGUAAUCUGACAUUUUAAUGUAGCUACUCUUAUUUAUUUUUUCUUUCUGAGGUAUUAAAAUAUCUGGACUGAGUUUUGCCAAAUGUUAAAGGGAGAAGAGUUACUGAAGACUUUGAACACUUGCUUUUUGUGAUUGCUUAUGUCAUUAGUGCCUCAUGACUGUGUUUGAUGUCCUUUAUUGAUACAAAGUGAGCCUGUGCCUUCAUUAUCUUGCCCAUUUUAAUACAAAUGGAAACCUGGUGUUUGAAAAUCUCUGAACUGUGUGGGUUUUGGAGGAAUAUACCUGAAUUUUAUUCAAUAACAGUUUCUGGACAGGAAGAAAAAUACAGUUACAUAUUUAUAAAA